AGUUAGCUCCGCAAGGACCCGGACGCGACCAGGGGAGGCAGAAGGUGAGGGGUCUGGGAGUCCUGGGCGGGGCCGGGGCGUGUCCGGAGCCUCGAAUCUGUGCGCGCAGGCGGGAGCUGGCUGCGGAUGCGCCGUUCUGAAUGUGUCUUUGUGGCUGUGUGGCUGGGUGUGGGUGUCUGCAACUGUGCACGUGUAACCGCCUGUCUCCAGGGUGUCUGGUGGUUUUUGUGUAACCAUGUGUGAUAGAGAGUAUCGGGGUGCAGGGUCCUUGUGACCGGGGGUGAUACUGCGUGUGUCCCCGUUGUAUAUGUGGCCUGUUCGCCCUGUUCCUGGGGUGUGAGUACAGUUGUGACUGUGUGACCACUGCGGGUGUGCGGUUGUGAUUCAUGUCUCCAAGGUGUGUGCGUGGUUUUGGUUGUGUGACACUGUGGCCGUGUGCAAUUGCCUGUGCCUGUGACUGUGUGGUGACGCCGCUUGUGUAUUCCUGUAUCCCUUGGUGUGUGUGUUUGUGUGUAUGUGUGUGGUGCUGUGUAUGCGGGAGUGGGGUGCCACUGCUUGUGUGGGUUGCUUGUGUGAGUGUGACUGUGUGUAUGUCCACAGUGAAAGUUCAGUUGUGACUGGGUGCCGUAAAGUACCAGUGAUGGCGUGUGUCCCCUGAGUGGGUGUGUGACUGUGACUAUAUGAGGCAUUUGUGGGUGUUGGUGUGUGGGGCUUGUGACUAUACGGGAGUAACUGUAUCACAGUGGAGAGUAGAUUGUGUGACUGGGUGUGUCUUAGCGGGUGUGUGAUUGUGACUGGAAAGAUAUUGUGACUGGAAAGGUAUAGAGGUGUCUGUGAUUGUGUCCUGUGUCUCAGGAGUGGAUGUAGGGCCGGGUGUGGUGGCUCACAUCAGCCCUUUGGGAGGCCGAGGUGGGAGGAUCACUUGAGCCCAGGAGUUCGAGACCAGCCUGGCCUGUACAAAAAAAAAAAAAAAAAAUUAAUGGCUGGCACGGUGGCUCACACCUGUAAUCCCAGCACUUUGGGAGGCCGAGGCGGGUGGAUCACCUGAGGUCAGGAGUUCUAGACCAGCCUGGCCAACACGAUAAAACCCUGUCUCUACUAAAAAUACAAAAAUUAGCUGGGCGUGGUGGCAGGUGCCUGUAAUCCCAGCUGCUCAGGGGGCUGAGGCAGGAGAAUCGCUUGAACCCAGGAGGCAGAGGUUGCAGUGAGCCGAGAUCGCGCCAUCGCACUCCAGCCUGGGGGACAAGAGCGAGACUUCGUCUCAAAAACAAACAAACAAAAAAUUAAAAAUUAUCUGAGUGUGGUGGCCCACACCUGUGGUCCCAGCUACCCGGGAAGCUGAGGUGGGAGGAUCUCGAGCUUGAGAGGUCAAGGCUGCAGUGAGCCGUGUUUGAACCACUGCAUUCCAGUCUAGGUGACAGAGCGAGACCCUGUCUCAAAAAAAUAAAAGAGUGGAUGUGUGGUUAUGUUUGUGUGACACUGACUGUAUGUGCAGCACCAAGUGUGCCAGUGACUCUAGUGCUUGACCCAUGCAGAACCUUUGAAGUUAGGACAGAUUCUGGCCCUGGACAGGAGUGACCUCAGCCUUCUGAGUGACACUGGAUUUAGGCAGAUGCCUGGUGUUCUGUGACCACACUUCCCUAUAUGGACUCUGCACUUGUCCAAGAGAAGAAUCCAGAGAAAUCAGAGCAGGUCAAAUAGUUCUAAAAGCCAUGGCCCAGGGACUGGUGACAUUCAGGGACGUGGCCAUAGAGUUCUCUCUGGAAGAAUGGAAGUGCCUGGAACCUGCUCAGAGGGACUUGUACAGGGAGGUGACUCUGGAGAACUUUGGUCACUUGGCCUCACUAGGACUCUCCAUUUCUAAGCCUGAUGUCGUCUCCUUAUUGGAGCAAGGGAAAGAGCCCUGGAUGAUUGCAAAUGAUGUGACAGGACCAUGGUGCCCAGACUUGGAGUCCAGGUGUGAGAAAUUUCUACAAAAAGACAUUUUUGAAAUCGGGGCAUUCAACUGGGAGAUAAUGGAAAGCCUUAAAUGCAGUGACCUGGAGGGCUCCGAUUUUAGAGCUGACUGGGAAUGCGAAGGCCAGUUUGAGAGACAAGUCAAUGAAGAGUGCUAUUUUAAGCAAGUGAACGUCACCUAUGGACAUAUGCCCGUGUUCCAGCAUCACACGUCUCACACUGUACGUCAGAGCAGGGAGACUGGUGAGAAACUGAUGGAAUGUCAUGAAUGUGGGAAAGCAUUUAGCCGUGGCUCACACCUUAUUCAACAUCAGAAAAUUCACACUGGUGAAAAACCCUUUGGAUGUAAGGAAUGUGGGAAGGCCUUCAGCCGUGCCUCACACCUUGUUCAGCAUCAGAGAAUUCACACGGGUGAGAAACCUUAUGACUGUAAGGACUGUGGGAAGGCCUUUGGUCGUACAUCAGAACUUAUUCUACAUCAGAGACUUCAUACUGGUGUCAAACCUUAUGAAUGUAAAGAAUGUGGGAAGACCUUUAGGCAGCAUUCACAGCUGAUUCUGCAUCAAAGAACUCACACAGGCGAGAAACCCUACGUAUGUAAAGACUGUGGCAAGGCUUUCAUUCGUGGCUCCCAACUCACUGUGCAUCGGAGAAUCCACACAGGGGCCAGACCCUAUGAGUGUAAAGAAUGCGGGAAAGCCUUUAGACAGCACUCACAGCUGACUGUACACCAGCGAAUCCACACUGGUGAGAAACCCUACGAGUGUAAGGAAUGCGGAAAGGGCUUUAUUCACAGCUCAGAAGUUACUCGACAUCAAAGAAUUCAUUCUGGGGAGAAACCCUAUGAGUGUAAGGAAUGUGGGAAGGCCUUCAGACAGCACGCACAGCUCACACGACAUCAGAGAGUCCAUACUGGCGACAGACCCUAUGAAUGUAAGGACUGCGGGAAGGCAUUUAGUCGUAGCUCAUACCUCAUUCAACAUCAAAGAAUUCAUACAGGUGACAAACCCUACGAAUGUAAGGAAUGUGGGAAGGCCUUUAUUCGUGUUUCACAACUGACUCAUCAUCAGCGAAUUCACACUUGUGAGAAACCCUAUGAAUGCAGGGAGUGUGGAAUGGCCUUUAUUCGUAGUUCACAACUUACCGAACAUCAGAGAAUUCAUCCUGGUAUCAAACCUUACGAAUGUAGAGAGUGUGGGCAGGCAUUUAUUCUUGGCUCACAACUCAUUGAACACUACAGAAUUCAUACUGGUUAGAAAGCCUUGAGUGUAAGGGAUAAAGAUAAGCCUUUAUGUGGAGUUCACAUCUGGCUCAGUACUAGGUAAUUUUUAAUGUAGUGUAAUUAAUGUCAGAAAACACCUGUCACUUCCAUCAUAGAACAUCAGAAAACUCACACCCAAAGAAAAUUAAAUAAAUGUGGGAAUUCUUUUUGCCUCACUCACUGUUUCCUAAGCAUCAGAUAAUCUAUGCUAAAAAAAAAUGAAUAUAGAAAAGCUGCUUCUUGCCAUUCAAAAUAUGUUAAAUUUCUGACAAUUCCUAAUACAAAAAUGACCCGAUUAAAAGAUUCUGUGGCCAGGCGUGGUGGCUCAUGCCUGUAAUCCCAGCACUUUGGGAGGCCAAGGCCGGCAGAUCAUUUGAGGUCAGGAGUUUGAGACCAGCCUG